AGUUGGCUCAGCUCUCCAGAGCUCCCGGACAGCAGCCGGAUCCCGGCCGGCUCCUGGGGCACUAGGACAGACCCCCGCGGCUAGCAGCCCGGCCUGGGGGGCGGAACACUCUCUUCUUGUCCCGCCCCACCUUCCUCCGGGCCGCAACCACCCCAGCCCAUCGCUGGGACGUGGCCGCGGGUGCCGAGAGCGCUGCCGGCGCCGUGGGGGCCAUCCCGGUCCUGGCCCCGACGGCGCCCCAGGACCUGCGAUAGCCGUAAGUAGCGACUAUGGGGGCUAGGAGAGUCCAAGAAGUGGGGAGCUGGGACGCCCGGCCUCCUGCGUCCCAGCUCUCCACUUCCAGACCCGGCUGGACUCGGGACUAGAAAAGGUGGCCUGGUGCCGCCGCUGCCUUCCAGUGUGCUCACUGGCCCUCGUGGCGGGGAGCCCAGACGCGGCUCCUAGGCGGCCCUAGACAAGUACGGCCGAGACGCUGUCACCCCAGGGGGCUGCCCCACCUGAGCAUCAUCCCACGGGCCCGCCCAGCCCCACCUGGAGAGCCGCAGGCUCCAAAGUCUUCCCCAUUCUCGGGGACCAGGUUCCGGGGUCGCGCUGAGGGCCCCUGAACCCUCUUGGACUGCCUGGCAGCGGCUUCUUCCUACCACCACGGCUCACCAUCCAGACGCGCCGCCCGGCUGGCCCCACCGGGAGAGGCUCCCUCCCUCCCCUUUCUCCCCGAACCCUCAUCUUAGAAGCCCUCGGAUUCAGUCUGGAUCCCAAAGAAGGGCUGAAUUCGGAGGACCUCUCUUUGCCCCCAAAGUCGGUUUUCUGACACACAUUCCCACGCACAGCUGGUAGGGGCAGGAGGGUCGAGGAUGCUCUGGGCUGCUGCGGCACAGGGCAGGCUGGUUGGUCACUAACCGGAUUUCCCGGACAGACAACUCUGGCGCUGUGGGCGGGUGGCCUGGGAGCCCAGAUCCCUGUCCCUGGCUUAGGACCCCGGGAGGAGACCGAGGGGGUGGGUAAAACGUGACUGAGAAACUUGAUCGCGCCCAUCUUUGGGGCAAAGAGAUUUGGAGGCCGCAAUUAUUCAGACAGUUCCACGAAGUGGUUGAGGUUUCUCUCUUUCUCCUGAUUUUCCAGAAACUUUUGCAGAGUUUGGACAGGCAAAGGAAAACGUGCAGCCCGCGGAUCUCCGGGCCUCAGAGAGCAGGGAGUCGGGGAGACUGAGGCCCCGCUCCGAGAGCGCGGAGGAAGCGCGCCCAGCCGGCUUCCUGUGGGGGCUCGGGCCUCGGGCGCCCCGCGGACAGACGUGUCCGGCUCCUGGCUGGGCCAAGCCCGGCGCGGGGGAGGGGACCCGCAGAGGGGCGACUGAGAAGGUCCGGGGCCGAUGUACCAGGUGAGCGGCCAGCGCCCCUCUGGCUGCGACGCGCCCUAUGGAGCCCCCAGCGCAGCCCCGGGCCCAGCCCAGACCCUAUCCCUCCUUCCUGGGCUGGAGGUAGUAACAGGAUCCACUCACCCUGCGGAGGCAGCACCAGAGGAGGGCUCCCUGGAGGAGGCGGCAACCCCCAUGCCCCAAGGCAAUGGCCCUGGCAUCCCCCAGGGCCUGGACAGCACUGACCUCGACGUCCCCACAGAAGCUGUGACAUGCCAGCCUCAGGGGAACCCCUUGGGCUGCACCCCACUUCUGCCGAAUGACUCUGGCCACCCCUCAGAGCUGGGCGGCACCAGACGGGCGGGGAAUGGUGCCCUGGGUGGCCCCAAGGCCCACCGGAAGUUGCAGACACACCCAUCUCUCGCCAGCCAGGGCAGCAAGAAGAGUAAGAGCAGCAGCAAAUCCACCACCUCCCAGAUCCCCCUCCAGGCACAGGAAGACUGCUGUGUCCACUGCAUCCUGUCCUGCCUGUUCUGCGAGUUCCUGACGCUGUGCAACAUCGUCCUGGACUGCGCCACCUGUGGCUCCUGCAGCUCGGAGGACUCGUGCCUCUGCUGCUGCUGCUGUGGCUCUGGCGAGUGUGCCGACUGCGACCUGCCCUGCGACCUGGACUGCGGCAUCCUGGAUGCCUGCUGCGAGUCCGCGGACUGCCUGGAGAUCUGCAUGGAGUGCUGUGGGCUCUGCUUCUCCUCCUGAGCCUCUGUCGGGGGCUAAGCCAGCCUGGCGCCCCUGCAGAUUCCAGCAGGGUCCCUCUGAGUGGGGCCAGGCCCAGGACUGUCACACAAGGCUUGAGAAGCCCCCUCUCCCUGGUCCUCUCCUACCCACCCAUGUCCUCUCAGAACCCCAGCCUUGAAAAUAGUGGGGGGCACUCAGAGGGGCCACCUCCUCAGCCGUGGGUGGUGGGCCCAUGGCAGAGAAGCCUGAACUCUUUACUGGGUUACCAGGUUCAUACAUUGCUGAGGACCUGACAGGACAACCUAGGGGCAGGGCUGGGGUGGGGACCGCAGGGGGCAGCCAGGGCUGGGGAACACUGUGAAAGUUACUUGGGGAGGGUGGGCCGGUGGGGCCGUAGCUCUCUACCUCUCCCUGCUCCUGGUGCCUGCCUCUCUCCUCCACCCCAGGCUUAGAGGACAGAAAAAUGUGAAGAGACGCCCCACCCACCCUCAGCCAGCCCUCUCCAGUCUCCUUUCCUAGGCUUUUUUGGGGGCCUAACCCACGCAGUGACCCCAGAGGGCAGGGCUAGGCGAGAGCCUGGGGUGGGGCGGGAGGGGGAACAGUAUGGAAAAGACUGGAAGGGGAAAGGAAGGGAAGGGAGGGAGGGUCUGUUCUAUCUGUUGCUGUAAAUAAAGAUAUUUGUCCAUCUCA